UUCCUCCCCUCGCAGACCGUGCACUCCUGCAGGGGGCCCCGGAUGCGAUGGAGCUGCGCGAGCUGACGCCCUGGGCUGGGCGGCCCCCAGGUCCGCGCCGUCGGGCGGGGCCCCGGCGGCGGCGCGCGCGUGCGCGGUUGGGGGCGCGGCCUUGCGGGCUGCGCGAGCUGGAGGUGCGCGUGAGCGAGCUGGGCCUGGGCUACGCGUCCGACGAGACGGUGCUGUUCCGCUACUGCGCAGGCGCCUGCGAGGCUGCCGCGCGCGUCUACGACCUCGGGCUGCGACGACUGCGCCAGCGGCGGCGCCUGCGGCGGGAGCGGGUGCGCGCGCAGCCCUGCUGCCGCCCGACGGCCUACGAGGACGAGGUGUCCUUCCUGGACGCGCACAGCCGCUACCACACGGUGCACGAGCUGUCGGCGCGCGAGUGCGCCUGCGUGUGACCCUACCUCACUCGGCCGGCGCGGCGGCCACUCCCCCCGCCUCGACGGCACCACUGGCCGGCCCCGCGAAAGACUGCGCGUGCGUAGAGCACGCCGGCGCGGCCCCGGGACUCUCGCGAUAACUGUACUGAGAUAAAGUGUGGCAACUCGA